AGGACCGCGGCCGGUGCCCCAGCCGAAGCCGGAGUCGCGCGGCCGGGAGCACGGGCGCCGGCAUAGUACAAUGAGGCAGCCAGCGGAUCUUGGGUGAGCAGUCUCAGGGCCAGGCGGGGGCGGUGGAGGGAGCGCCCCGCGGAUAAGGCCCGGGCUGGGCGCGGAUCGACCCCGCGGGCUUCAAAGUACCGGUCGGGUCCGGCGGCCCUUGGCGUGGCGGGGCUCGGCCCCCCACCCCGCUGUCAUGGUUCAGGUAUUGAAGGGGACGCCCACCCGCGACACCCCCGGGCAAUCCCUUCCUUCGGGGCCCCGCCGGAUGGCUCGGGCUCGACUCCGGCGGGAGGAGCUGCCGGCCCCGUCCCCUCAGCCUGCGGUCCCCGGCCCCGGGCAGGGAGGCACCGUCACGCGCAAACUAGAGGAAAACGGCUUGCAAUUUUAUGAAUGGGGCCCCGGGUUCCUGCCGCCCCCCUCACCGGCGACGCGAAAUGCUUGAAAGUCGAGAACCGCAGUUACUUUUACUCGAAUCUGUCAGAGAGCCUGAGCCCUUGUGAAGCCGGCAAUGACAAGUCUGUAUGGUCGCCAUGCCGAGAAAACCACUGACAUGCCAAAACCAUCAGCCCCUAAAGUGCACGUGCAGAGGUCCGUGUCCCGAGAUACCAUCGCCAUUCACUUCUCGGCAUCCGGCGAGGAGGAGGAGGAAGAGGAGGAGGAGUUCAGGGAGUACUUUGAGGAGGGGCUGGAUGACCAAAGCAUUGUAACAGGGCUGGAAGCCAAGGAAGACCUCUAUCUUGAACCCCAAGUUGGCCAUGACCCCGCCGGCCCUGCUGCCUCGCCUGUCCUGGCAGAUGGACUGUCCGUGUCCCAGGCCCCUGCCAUUUUGCCCGUCUCCAAGAACACUGUAAAGCUGUUGGAGUCCCCUGUUCCAGCAGCACAAGUAUUAAGUACAGUGCCAUUGGCUGUGUCCCCAGGGUCGUCUUCGUCGGGGCCCUUAGCUAGCUCUCCCAGUGUGUCAUCCCUUUCUGAGCAGAAAACCAGUUCUUCCUCCCCAUUGUCCUCUCCUUCUAAGUCUCCCAUCCUCUCAUCCAGUGCCUCAACCUCCACCCUUUCCAGUGCAAAACCCUUCAUGAGCCUUGUGAAGUCCCUGUCGACCGAGGUGGAGCCAAAAGAAUCCCCACACCCCGCAAGGCACAGGCACUUGAUGAAGACAUUAGUCAAGUCUCUGUCCACGGACACUUCCCGGCAGGAGUCGGAUACAGUGUCCUAUAAGCCACCUGAUUCCAAACUGAACUUACACCUGUUCAAGCAGUUCACACAGCCCCGAAACACAGGUGGAGAUUCCAAAACUGCACCUUCUUCCCCACUGACUUCUCCCUCUGAUACUCGUUCCUUUUUUAAAGUGCCCGAAAUGGAGGCUAAAAUUGAAGAUACUAAACGACGCCUUUCAGAAGUCAUCUAUGAGCCUUUUCAGCUCCUUAGUAAAAUUAUAGGGGAAGAAAGUGGCAGCCAUAGGCCCAAAGCCUUAUCUUCAAGUGCUUCAGAACUCUCCAAUCUGUCCAGCUUGAAUGGGCACUUGGAAAGCAAUAACAACUACAGCAUCAAGGAGGAGGAGUGUGAUUCUGAGGGGGAUGGCUACGGAAGUGAUUCCAACAUCCCCAGAAGUGACCACCCAAAGUCCACUGGUGAGCCCACAAGAGAGAUAGAACUGAAAAGUUCCCAGGGGAGCAGUCUGAAGGAUUUAGGCCUGAAGACAAGUUCUCUAGUUCUGGAGAAAUGUUCUUUGUCUGCCUUAGUGAGCAAAGAAGAUGAAGAGUUUUGUGAACUGUACACUGAGGACUUCGAUUUGGAAACGGAGGGGGAGAGUAAAGUUGAUAAGCUCUCAGAUAUUCCUCUCAAGCCAGAGGUGCUCGCGGAAGAUGGUGUGGUCCUUGACAGUGAGGACGAGGUGGACUCGGCCGUGCAGCACCCGGAAUUGCCAGUGAAGACGUUGGGCUUCUUUAUAAUGUGUGUCUAUGUGUACCUCAUCCUCCCCCUCCCCCACUAUGUGAGUGGACUCUUUCUGGGAAUUGGCCUUGGAUUCAUGACUGCAGUUUGCGUGAUUUGGUUUUUUACACCACCAAGUGCUCAUAAAUAUCACAAGUUACACAAAAAUCUGCGACACUGGAACACAAGAUCUCUGGAUAUCAAAGAACCUGAAAUACUGAAGGGAUGGAUGAAUGAGAUUUACAACUAUGAUCCAGAAACCUACCAUGCGACUUUGACACAUUCAGUCUUUGUUCGACUUGAGGGUGGAACCUUAAGACUUUCAAAGCCCAAUAAAAAUAUAUCCAGGAGGGCCAGCUACAAUGAACCCAAGCCAGAGGUCACCUACAUCAGCCAGAAAAUCUAUGACCUCUCAGACAGCAAGAUUUAUCUUGUACCUAAAACUUUGGCUCGAAAGCGAAUCUGGAAUAAAAAGUACCCCAUUUGUAUCGAGCUUGGUCAGCAAGAUGACUUUAUGUCUAAAGCUCAGACUGAUAAGGAGACUUCAGAAGAGAAGCCGCCAGCUGAGGGAAGUGAGGACCCUAAGAAGCCACCCCGCCCUCAGGAGGGAACAAGAUCUAGCCAGCGAGAUCAGAUACUCUAUCUCUUUGGGAGAACUGGCCGAGAAAAAGAGGAAUGGUUUAGGAGAUUUAUUCUGGCAUCUAAGCUAAAGUCGGAAAUCAAGAAGUCAUCGGGUGUCUCUGGAGGUAAACCAGGGCUUUUGCCUGCACACAGCAGACACAACAGUCCGUCCGGGCACCUGACCCACAGCCGCAGCAGCAGCAAAGGCAGUGUGGAGGAGAUCAUGUCACAGCCAAAGCAGAAGGAGCUGGCAGGCAGCGUGCGGCAGAAGAUGCUUCUCGACUACAGCGUGUACAUGGGCAGGUGUGUCCCCCAGGAAAGCCGAAGCCCCCAGAGGAGCCCCCUGCAGAGUGCGGAGAGCAGCCCCACAGCUGGGAAGAAGUUGCCAGAGGUUCCACCCUCUGAGGAGGAAGAACAGGAAGCCUGGGUGAAUGCCUUGCUUGGAAGAAUAUUUUGGGACUUCUUAGGAGAGAAAUACUGGUCUGAUCUGGUGUCUAAGAAGAUCCAAAUGAAACUCAGCAAAAUAAAGCUCCCCUACUUUAUGAAUGAGCUCACUCUGACGGAACUUGACAUGGGCGUGGCUGUGCCAAAAAUCCUCCAGGCCUUCAAGCCUUACGUUGAUCACCAAGGACUCUGGAUUGAUUUGGAAAUGUCCUACAAUGGGUCCUUUCUGAUGACUCUCGAGACCAAAAUGAAUUUGACCAAACUAGGUAAAGAGCCUCUUGUUGAAGCCCUGAAGGUUGGAGAAAUUGGCAAAGAAGGUUGCAGGCCCCGGGCAUUCUGUCUGGCGGACAGCGAUGAGGAAUCCUCCAGCGCUGGCUCCUCCGAGGAAGACGAUGCCCCAGAGCCCAGCGGGGGAGACAAACAGCUCCUCCCAGGGGCUGAAGGGUACGUUGGAGGUCAUCGAACAAGUAAGAUUAUGAGGUUUGUUGAUAAAAUUACCAAGUCAAAAUAUUUCCAAAAAGCAACAGAGACAGAGUUUAUUAAAAAGAAGAUCGAAGAAGUCUCCAACACACCCCUGCUGCUCACUGUUGAAGUACAAGAAUGUAGAGGAACCUUGGCGGUCAACAUUCCACCACCCCCGACUGACCGAGUAUGGUAUGGUUUCCGAAAGCCACCACAUGUGGAGCUGAAAGCUCGGCCAAAACUUGGAGAGAGAGAAGUGACUUUAGUUCAUGUGACAGACUGGAUAGAGAAGAAACUGGAGCAAGAGUUUCAGAAAGUUUUUGUCAUGCCAAACAUGGAUGAUGUUUAUAUCACUAUAAUGCACUCAGCCAUGGACCCUCGCUCUACUUCCUGCCUCCUGAAAGACCCACCUGUGGAGGCUGCUGAUCAGCCAUGAUGGGUGAUGUCAGAUGUUCCCCAUAUUGUGACAUCGAGCUGGAUGUGUGGGGUUCUUGGCCGCCAUCUGUACUGUAGCACUGGCCUCUGUGCCACAGCUACUGUUUCUUAAAGGACUGCUUCUGCCCUCUGCCUGCCAGUGCCCAUUCCACUGUGAGGUGUCAUUCCCUGCAUCUAGUGACAACUGUCUGGAUUGCCUGCUGCAAAGCUUUGAUUUGGCAAAGGAGACCAUGGAAGAAUCAUGGUGGAUCCAGAAGUUAUACGUGACCCACACCAUGGCUUUUAAAAGUCUACCCAUGUUUGUGGCAGCAAAUGAGCACAGUAAGAGCAAAGCUGAACAACUUGCCUCCUCUACUCCUCCAAAGCUUUUCUUCAGGCAGCCGGUGCACAGUGGACUUUUUCACUUCUAUACUUUGUAUGCGGCCUUCCACACUUCCAGAGAAUGUCAGUGUGCAAUGUGUCUGGAGGGUGGGGAGAGGAAUUCUGUGAGCCUUUUCAUUUCGGUGACAGAAGAGAUGGGCAGAGCAACUUAUUUUCCACAUUAAAUUGUGCAUUUGGGAAGCAAGUAGCCAUAGUACACACACAACACGCUAUCAGCUUGGGUAAGGACAGUGGGAUUUAUGUGAACAUCAGGCAAAGCCAUGAGAUCAAACCAUCCCAAGCCUUUCACCAAUGAGGUACAACCACCUGGGGGCUAGCUAAUCUUGAAUGUUUUCCUGAGACAGGAGCGUAUGUGAAAACAUCAAACACUGCACAUGACAGGAUGGGUCCUCUCAUACAGAUGGGAUGGGGUUAGAAAGCCAGAGCCAGUUUUUCCAUCUGGCGUUUCCUGUGUCCUCCAGGUUUAUAUGGGAAUCGAAACAGUUUGUUAAUCUGAUUGGGAGAGUUCCAUGGGCAGAUUUCCCUUCCUGAAGGCCAAAACGGAGAACUGCUCUCUUUAAUUAUUUCAAGAGUCAAGACCAAAAGUUUGCUCAGCAUCACACUACAUCUCAAAAUUAAUGUUGCCAACUUAAUUUUGUGCAUUUGUGUCAGAAUGUUUAGUUUACAAGGUUGGGGGCUCUCUUUGCUUCGAGAAGUAAACCUAAUACCAUUUUUUUAUUGUUUAAAGCUGCAUUCAACGUCAAAAUUACCUUGGGUAACUUUUGAUAACUUACAUGUGUGGACAAAGCUAAUAGUGGUUUUUUAAACAGCACCUUGCCUGAACAUGACUUUAAAGAAAUUAAUAUAUUGAAAACAUGUUUGAACCCUUAUUUUAAUUGCACCAUUAAAACAUUUGACUUAAAUUGUUUGACCAUUCCAGUUGGUGUACUGUUCUGAUUUUUCGUUGUGUAGGCCGAUCUGCCUGUCAGAGUCCACGUGUCCUGGUCACUGGUCUUUAUAAUUGUUGUGCAAUAACUAAAGGCUAAGGACUAGAUGCACUAUCGUGUAAAGAGAUUACACAUGACUGUACCAUGUUGCACUUAAUCAAAUAGUAUGUGGGGAUUUAAAAUCGCUUGCAUUGUUUCACAAAAUAAAUAUCUCAAUGUCAAAUACUAGAUAAGCAUCUAAGUCAUUUCUACGGAAUCCUGUUCAGAUAGGGGCACAAUAAAAUGAGUACAGAGCACCGGGGCCCUCACCUGGCAAUCGCAGCUUUCAUUUACUGCGUUGAUCACUGCCCAGUCCUAAGGCUACAAAGCCAUCCUCACUACAUCCUUCAAACUAUGUGCCAUUAUCUUCAGCCCACAUUUAAAGAAUCCAGUGAAA